AUAUUAGCAGCGGUUAUUCGGUGAGCGGUGGUGGUUUAUUCUUCCGUGGAGUUAAGGGCUCCGUGGACAUCUCAGGUCUUCAGGGUCUUCCAUCUGGAACUAUAUAAAGUUCAGAAAACAUGUCUCGAAGAUAUGACUCCAGGACCACUAUAUUUUCUCCAGAAGGUCGCUUAUACCAAGUUGAAUAUGCCAUGGAAGCUAUUGGACAUGCAGGCACCUGUUUGGGAAUUUUAGCAAAUGAUGGUGUUUUGCUUGCAGCAGAGAGACGCAACAUCCACAAGCUUCUUGAUGAAGUCUUUUUUUCUGAAAAAAUUUAUAAACUCAAUGAGGACAUGGCUUGCAGUGUGGCAGGCAUAACUUCUGAUGCUAAUGUUCUGACUAAUGAACUAAGGCUCAUUGCUCAAAGGUAUUUAUUACAGUAUCAGGAGCCAAUACCUUGUGAGCAGUUGGUUACAGCGCUGUGUGAUAUCAAACAAGCUUAUACACAAUUUGGAGGAAAACGUCCCUUUGGUGUUUCAUUGCUGUACAUUGGCUGGGAUAAGCACUAUGGCUUUCAGCUCUAUCAGAGUGACCCUAGUGGAAAUUACGGGGGAUGGAAGGCCACAUGCAUUGGAAAUAAUAGCGCUGCAGCUGUGUCAAUGUUGAAACAAGACUAUAAAGAAGGAGAAAUGACCUUGAAGUCAGCACUUGCUUUAGCUAUCAAAGUACUAAAUAAGACCAUGGAUGUUAGUAAACUCUCUGCUGAAAAAGUGGAAAUUGCAACACUAACAAGAGAGAAUGGAAAGACAGUAAUCAGAGUUCUCAAACAAAAAGAAGUGGAGCAGUUGAUCAAAAAACAUGAGGAAGAAGAAGCCAAAGCUGAGCGUGAGAAGAAAGAAAAAGAACAGAAAGAAAAGGAUAAAUAGAAUCAGAGAUUUUAUUACUCAUUUGGGGCACCAUUUCAGUGUAAAAGCAGUCCUACUCUUCCACACUAGGAAGGCUUUACUUUUUUUAACUGGUGCAGUGGGAAAAUAGGACAUUACAUACUGAAUUGGGUCCUUGUCAUUUCUGUCCAAUUGAAUACUUUAUUGUAACGAUGAUGGUUACCCUUCAUGGACGUCUUAAUCUUCCACACACAUCCCCUUUUUUUGGAAUAAAAUUUGGAAAAUGGAAAUGAAGGAAUAAAUUCUCUGUAGCAGUAAUUGUUAAAUAUACAAAAACUGACAGGGCGAUUACUUUUUGCACAUUGUGGCUUACAGUCCUUUCACAAAGAUGGGCACGUUCCUCAGGCUGGCCAGAUUAUUCGUCUCUGUCUGCAGGAAUUGGUUUGAGAAUGAACACGUGAGCUGAACAAAGCCAGAAUUGAUGUGUGGGUGUGGAUCUCGCAGCUAGGACUGAGGCUGCCCACAGGCAGCAGCUCAAGCUGCGCGGAAGAUGAGGUGUAGAAGUUAAGGCCACAGAGGAAAAGUGGAACCAAGAGAUGAGAACAGUUACGUGUUGGCUGAAGGGAGCUCUGUUGCUGGGGUUUGUUCAACCUGAGUUCCCUUGGCUAUCUGUGGCUUCAUGACAGAAGUGAUACAGGGCAGUGGUACUUAAUGCGUAGCCAUGGUGCUUUAGCAUCACCUAUGCAGAUUCUGAUGUCCCAUCCCAGAUCUACUGAAUUAAAAUCUCUGAGGGUGAAACCCAGUAAUCUGUUCUAACAAGCUCUGCAUGUGAUUCUUAGGAAUGCUAAGUAAAACUUUAAGAAGUUUUUGUUGCAUAUUAGAAUCACCUAGGAAGCUUUUGCAGCUUGUAAGCAUGCUGUAUCGAUUAACUCAAGCUCUGUGGUGGAACCCAGAUAUUAACAUUGCUUAAACUCUUCAGGUGAUUUCCAUCAGCUAGGGUGAGUGCAUUGAGCCAUCAUUUACCCUUCUCUCAGCUGUUGUCAACCAAAUAUGUGCUCCCAGUCUAAUUUCUCAUUGUAGAUUUUCUUAAUGCAGCUCCCUGCAGUUUUCUGUAUAGGCUAAAGUAUUUACAAGCCCUAUUUGCAGCACUUUUUUGAACUUCUAAAUUAUUCUCUUACUCUGUACAGCAGGUUCUCGUUAUUUUUGGUAGUUAUGUUCUAAAGUCACCACAAAAACUAACAAAAUACUGAACUCUUGCACCUAGAGAAAGUACUGGGUUAGGGUCCUACAAGCCACUGGUCACAUUUUUAUCAACUGAUCAGUACAUAACCUGUUUUUUGUGUAUUUCUACUUAAAGACACCUUUUUAAAUGUGUAUUGUGGAUUCAUUAACAUAGAACUCAGCCAACAGCUCUUUACGUGAAUGUUUUUGUUUUGUUUUGUUUUUUGAGACUGGGUCUUGCUCUGUCACCCAGGCUGGAGUGCAGUGGCGUGAUCAUAUUUCACUGCAGGCUCAAACGGUCUUCCUGCCUUGACCUCCCAAAGUGUUGACAUCACAGCCCUCUUAUGCUUAGGAACAACACUAAACAGUGUUUUUUUCAUAGAGACGGUGAGCAGGGAAGGUCUCACCAUGUUUCCCAUGCCGGUCUCAAGCUCCUGGACUCAAGCGAUCCUCCUGCCUCAGCCUCCCAAAGUGCUGACAUCACAGCCCUCUUGUGCUUAGGAACAUUAAACAGCACUUCAGCACUAUACCUGGGUGCCAUUUGAAAUAGUAAAAUCACUAAGAAAAAUGCAAAAAUAAACGGCACAAGGUAGACUGCAGGAACACUUACACGGUGUGAGAGCUGAAACAAGAAUUCAGAGUGUCGCCUUGCUCAACCUCAGAUGGGAACAUGUGCACCUGGGUACUCAAAAUUUUCACCACUCUGCAUGUCAACAAAUGACUAAAAGUACCACAAGUAUUGGUUUGGGGGUUACAUGUACAUUUUAUGAGAAUGCAAAUUUUGCAAAUUCACAAGUACAGAAUCAGCAAGUAGUGAAGAUGAAUGGCACGUCUUCACCCUCCAGUCUUGCUACACCCAGAGGUUGAGGUAGUCAAUAAAUCUUAUUAACUCUGUCUGCAGAAUUUACCCAUAAUCCAGCCACUUUCCACUGCAGGAACGCUGGUCCAAUUCACCAUUAUCUCUGACUUGGACUAUUGCAACAGCCUCCUAACUGGUUCCUUGCCUCCACUUCAUUCCCCACAGUCAAUUCUCCAGCAGCAGCCACAGUGAUCCUUUCAAAAUGUAAACGGUACUACUGCACAGUUUUGGCUCAAAACCCUCCAAUGGCUUCCCAUCUUGCUCAGUAAGAGUCAAAUUCUUUGUACUGGUUCAUGAGGUAUCCUGUAUUCUGGCCUUGUGCUACCUUCCAUGUGCUUCCUUCCUCACUCAUUCAUCCAAAUGAGCCUUCUCAUCAUUCCCUGAAUGUGCCAAGCUCCCCUCACAUCACUUGCCAAUCCCUCUGCCUUGGGAAUGCUCUUCCUGGGUAUCUAUUGCCCACUCCCUCAUCUCCAGGUCUCUGCUUGCAUGUCACCUUUUUUGGGGUACUUCUGUGAAGGAGCAAUCUCUUUCCCCUGCACACUCACAUUUUCUAUUCCCUAUACAUACCCUGUUGAGUUUUUCUCCAUAGCACUCAUCACCAGCUGGCAUAUUUGUUUCUUGUCUCUCCCCACUGGAAUACAGACUUCCAGAGCAGUACUUUGUUUUCAUUCAAUAGUCGUGUCUCGGUACCUAGAACAGAAACUGGCACGUGUUAGGCAACAAAUAAGUACUGAUGAAUGAAUAAAUACCCUGGAUAUGCUGGUGUGAAAUCCUAAAAAAUACCUGCUUUCCAUCCAGAUCAGUAGCACUGGUGGAUUUUCUGUAUCCUGACUACCCCUUCAACAUUUGCCUAAAGCUAGGACAACUUCUUCAAAGGCAAUAGUGAAUAAGAGAGCCUGGUAUAGUUUGCCGCCACAUUAGGAAAGUCUUCAGAAUUUGACCCUAACAGCAGGCAAAUUUCAACGUAUUCAUCUUUUUGUUGAAAUAAAUUCAUACUGUGAGGAAAAGCAAAAGAUAGGAGGUGAGGCAAAAGCUACUCUUUAACUGUGAGUUUUUUUUCCUUGCGAUGGGGUUUGGCUGCCUAGUCUAGAUUCUCACGCUAGCCCCACUUUCGUCUGCUCUGUGGCAUAUUUUUAACCUGAGUUGCAGGACAGGUGGUUUCCAGAGUGUUGCCUGAUGCAUCCCAAAUGCUGCCUUAGCAAUACACAUCUGAACAGGGGCCCAUCACUAAUAGCAAGCAUUUCAUUAAUCUGAGCAAAACUCAUGGGUUUUCACAGGGACCCUACCAGCUCAGAAGCACGUUGAUAUAAAUAAGUAGAAAACCAAAGACAGCUAAGUUUUAAAUCUUGAGUCAAAACUUUAAAAUCAAAGUCAAAUUGAUUUCAUUUUGGUGAGCUUUCAAAUCAUGCUUUUAAAAAUAAAUUAUGUAAAAAAA